CAAAUAUUCCAAAAUCAGAAAAAAAAAAAUCCAAAAUCUAAAACACUUUCAGUAUUAAGCAUUUCAGGUCAUGGAUACUGAAUGUGUAUCUUUAAUUUCUUGUUCUACUUUGUUUAAAAAAAAGGGGGAAAAUAGUAAUUCUACAGAUGAAUAAUAAUUGCUAAUGAUGAGCAAAUACUUCCUAUGACCCAGGAAUUCGUCUAAGCACUUCACAUAUAUCAAACUGGUUUAAUCUUUAUAAAUCAGUACUAUUAUUAUCCCCAUUUUACAGAUGAUGGAAAAAGGCACAGAGAGUUAGCCUGCCCAAGGUUACAUUCCUUUUAGUGGUGGAGACUGUAUUUGGCCUUUAUAGUCUGGCUUUUAACUGCUACACUAUAUCAAUGCAUUACAGGUAUAGUUUAUACACACACUAAAGAAGACAUGGAACUCCAGUCAGUGGGCUCAUAAAAGCUUUAGACCUUCAUCAAAAGAUUAGAAAAUAAAUGUUCAAUCACAGGUUUUAGGUUUCAAAAGUUUCAAAAGUUUAAAGUUUGCAAGUUAUCUUUCUUAAAAUUAUUUCCUUCUUUUAACUAAUUUUUAAAUUAAACUCCAGUUCAAUCACAUCCACUAGAAGGCUUCACUUUCUACAAAGGGGUAGGUAAAGGUGAUGAUCUUAAAUACCAUACUGGGAGUUGGGAUCUGUGUAGCACUAGAAUCAAGAGUUAUUGUAUAUACUUGAGAAGGAGCACAGCCUGAUUUAGUUGAUGUUUUGGAGGGGUAAUCUGGCAGUACAGCUUGGAUUAUUUUAGUGGGAAUGGAGAUGACAAAACAUGAAGAGAAUGGGAGAACUCACUUGGGUAAUAUAUCAGUUUCUGAAAUCAAUGUAUCAAGUGGUUUGGUUAUUAGUCAGGCUUAAGGUUUUAUUGGCCUUAGGACAUAGUCUCUAAGACCAUAUAUUAUCUUCAUUCAUUCAUUUAACCAACACCCACUGAGCACCAACUAUGCACUAGUGAUACAGGGGUGAACAAACAGACACAGUCCCUGCCUUUGCAGAACUUAUGUUCUGGUGGGUGAUACAGAGAAAUAACAAAUGAGGGCACAAAUAAUGAACUAUCAUUGUAAUGUGCUAACAAAGUAUGCAGAAUACUAUAAGAACAUACAAUCAAGAAUCUAAUCUAGUUUAUUUUAAAAAAAAGUGGGGGGAGCACUCAGAUGUUUAAACACAAAACAAUAAAAAUGAGGAUCUUGAGGGUUAUCUGUACACUUUUUAUUAACCCAUUUGGCCACAACAAUAACCCAGUAAAAGUGAUUUUACAUCUAGUUAACUAGUUGACUCAAUGUUAUUAUAACCCUGUAAUGUAUUUGUUGGGUGCCUGCUAUGUAGUGGGCUGUGUUCCAGGAGUGGGACAUAAAGCUAUGACAAGAUAGAUCAGGUCCUUGCCUUGACUGAGUCUGAAUACAUCACCUUCAUUUCCACCUCUGCUUCUAAGACAAUCAAAUACCUUCCCACUCAGAUAGGGAUUCAUCCUAUUUCUUGUAGUAAUUAUAAGUUCCCAGGGUUACAGAUUAGUAAAUGCCAUACCUAAAGACUUAGGAUACUGUGCAUAAAACACUUUCAAUAGUGUCUGUCAGACAGCAGAUGCGCAAUAAAUGUUGACUUUCGUUAGAAUUGUGUUAUUAUUAUAAUGCUAAAUCUCACGUCCUUUCUGGCACACUGGAGUUCAUCUCUUCAAUUAAAUUCCGUAAGCACAUAUUGUAAGUAGUCUAUCAGAAUUGAUAUACUACUUCAUGUUAAUGAUUGAGAUCAGUGAGGAAAACCACUUUAAUAUUGUCUAAUUCCUCUCUUAAUGCAUAGGAGCCAUGUGAACUUAGACAAGCAUCAACCUCUGUAAGCCUGUUGUCCUCAUAUUGAAAAAUCGAAUAACAAUACCUAUCUCAUUUAAUUGUUGUCAGCAAAAGUGGGCAGCAGAAGAGUGGGGAUCAAUAAAUGUUAGCCACAAAUCAUAACUAUUUGUAUUACUCUGAAAAAGAGGGGUUAACUUAUAGUUCAUGCAUGCUUCCAAAUGAAUGUGAAAGACUAAAGAAUGAGAAUUUUUUUGCUAUCAAAUUAAAAAAUUAACAGGCACAUUUAGAUUGCUGAAGAGAGAAAUUAGGAUAAGUUUUUUUUUUUUUUUGCUCAAUUAAAAACGUUUUCAAUGGCAUAUUUAAAACUACGUAUUCUUCCCCAUUAAGAUCUGCAGAGAAAAAAAAAUGAAGGGAGAAUAAUUGGGAACUCUUGUGAAAUCAUAAAUUAUUUAAGCAGAGUACCUACCACUAAGGAUUUGAGCAUGUAUGAGCGAUGAGGUGGAUUCUUAGAGCAGAGAUUCAGCAGUGAGACAGGCUAAUGGCAUGGGGAGAUGUGUUCUAUUAGACAACUGUAUUGUCCCCUUAAUUAUAUACAUAUAUAUGUAUAUAAUAUAUAUGUGUAUACAUAUGUAUACAUACAUGUAUAUAUAAAUAGAAUUCUUAAUCAUUUUAAGCAGUGUACAAGGAUAAUUAUUAGCAUGGGCUAUUUAACUCACUUUUAAAACGUGUAAAACAUUAUUGUAGGGUUGGGUCUUGAUUUGUUUCCCAUGAAACUGUUGGUAGUUUAGGGGCCAAAUUAACGAAAGACAUCUCAUUCUAGUGCUUGAGGCUCAGAAAUUGGAAAAACGGGCAACUAGGUCAAGCAGUGUUCUCAUAGCCUCACAGAUGAGCAUCCAAAGCAAGGGCCUCCUUCUAGUUGACUUGUGCCAAGGGACAGGAGAAGCGGAGUCUGCCUUCUGGGUCCAGAAGGGGGUUUUGUUAACAUGGAGUUGCUCAGCGCCCUUCAUAAAAAUUCUUCUGGCUGAGGGUUCUACGUUGGCAUACGGUUGGUUCCCUCUUCUUUUCCGAGGUGGCGAGUAUCUCUUCCUUUGCCAAGAUGGCGGCUCCAGAAUCCUCUGGAGGCGGCCCCCGUAGAUCGUCUCCGGACAAGAGGCUUGCUGAAAGCCUACUUCUUUCCUUUCACAUCAGACAAUGCACAGGGAACCGUUUACCCUUGAGAACCAAGGAAGGACGGCUUAGGCUACCCGCGAUCGCGAACCUUUGCCAAGAUGGUGGCCGCGGGGACGGGCUGGCGACACUGUACCCUACCAAGAUGGCGGCGGGCGGCUUCCGGGACGCGCUUCCCCAAUCGUCUUCAAGAUGUCAGAGCAGGGGGAGCCGCCGUCAGUCUGAGCGCGGCGGGAGGGGCAGGGGUCCUAUGAACGUGAUAGGGUGAGCAACGCACAGAGUCGAGGGCAGCAAAUGUCAAGAUUCGGGGGUGGGGCCUGCACCGGGAACUUGGACGCGGGCCCUGGCCGGGGUGGAAGAAGAGGUCAGGAGUUUCGGAAGGGGGGCUAUAUUUCGCCAGCAACUUACUAUUUCGCCUGCAACUUGCUUUUAAGCCUGCCGCCCCCUGCUUUCCUUAAUCAUAAUAAUAAAAAAAAAGUGCAAAGAAA